GUUGAAAUAAUUUCCAACUUAGAGAGAAGAUACAAAAAUAGUAGAAAAAUAGUUUCCAAUAAAAUCUUCAUCUAGCUAACAUUAAUAUCUUAUACAACCAUAGUACAAUGAUCAAAAUCAGAAAAUUAACAUUGGUACAAUACUAUUAAUAUAAACUACAGACCUUAUUCAUAUUCCAUCAGUUUCCCUCCAGUGCUCCUUUUCUAUUUCAGGAUCCAAUUCAGGAUCACAUAAAACAUCCAGUCAUUAUGAUUCCUUAAUUUCCUCCAAUAUGUGACAGUACCUCAUUUUUUCCCUUCUCUUUCAUGACCUUAACACAUUCAGUGGGUAAUGGAUAGUUACUUUGUAGACUUCCCCCAGUUUGGGUUUGUUUGAUGUUUUCUCAUGAAUAGCUUGAAGUUAUAAUUUCCAACAAGAAAAUUACAGAAGUGAUGCCAUGUCCUUCUCAGUGCAUCGCAUCAGAGGGUACAUGAUGAUCAGUAUCCUUAUCACUGGUGAUAUUUACUUGGAUCAUUUGGUAAGGUGGUCUCCACUGUUAAGUUAUUGUUUUUCUCUUUAUAAUUGAUGAAUGUUUUGGGGGAGAUAUUUUAAGACUAUACUAAUAUCCUGUUAUCUGCAAACUUUUGCCCAGUGAUUUUAGCCUAUGUAAAUUAAUCUUGCCAACAUUUUUUUUUUUUUUUACCUGGAUGUUUGCCUAAUGGUGAUUUUGUAUUUGAGGGAGACUUUCUGAUAUGAGGUUAAGAAUCCUGAGUUGUUAACUCUUGGAUAAAGAUCGAGAGACUUUUGCCCCCUUGGAAAGGUUUGGAAGGCUAGAGGGAGGUGUGGGGGCUUAAGUGGUAGAUAUAUGGGGCAGUGUGGGAUUGAGAGACUGAGUCAUAUUGAGUGAUAGGUGAGACUGGAACACUCGGUGGUGACCGAGAUAAAUAGGAAUGUGUAAGACAGGAUAGAAUUAGUACUUACAGGAGGUUAGCCAUGGUUCUGAAUUGCCACUUUCAUAAAGUUAACUUUUGGUGAAAAUAUAAAUUUGUGUAGAUCAGCUUGGCACUAUUAAGCAUGGUUUAAUCGUGAAUAGACUGAGCACAGUGGCUCGUGCCUGUAAUCCCAAUGCUUUGGGAGGCUGAGGUGGGAGGAUCACUUGAGGCCAGAAGUUUGAGAUCAGCCCGGGCAACACAGCAAGACCCCACCUCUAAAAAAAUAUUAGCUGAGCAUUGUGGUGUGCUCCUGUAGUCCCAACUACUUGGGAGGUUGAUGUAGGAGGAUCACUUGAACCCAGGAGGUCAAGGCUGCUGUCCAGCCUGGGCAACAAUGUGAGACCCUGUCUCAAGAAACAAAAACAAAAAAUUGCAUAUCUAUUUAUGGGAACCUAUAUUAGAAUAAAAUUCUACUUCUAGGUGUAUAUCUUAGAAAAAAUAUUUAUGUAUUUGCACAAGAUGUAUAUACCAGGAUGCUCACUGGAAAAAACUAUAAAUAUCCAUCCAUAAGAAUGUUAAAUGUAUUAUAUCCAUAUCAUAAAAUGCUAUUCAGCUGCCAAAAGGAAUAAGAUAUAUAUUUAUAAAUAUGGAAAAAUCUCAAAGAUGUGGUUAGAUGACAAAAAUCUAUUUUCAGAACAAAAUAUAGUAUCCCACUUAAAGAAAAAAGUCUGUUAGUUUAGGGUAGGAAAAGCUGUAGUUAAAAAACAUAAACACCAAAAUUUCAGUGACUUAAAGAACAAGAAGUUUAUAUCUUUCUUGUGGAAUGAUCCAGGGCUGAUGUUUGAGUCAGGUUAGCUUUCGCCCCCUGGCAUUAAAAGCUGCAGGCAAGGCCGGGCGCGGUGGCUCACGCCUGUAAUCCCAGCACUUUGGGAAGCCGAGGCGGGUGGAUCAUGAGGUCAGGAGAUCGAGACCAUCCUGGCUAACAAGGUGAAACCCCGUCUCUACUAAAAAUACAAAAAAUUAGCCGGGCGCGGUGGCGGGCGCCUGUAGUCCCAGCUACUCGGGAGGCUGAGGCAGGAGAAUGGCGUGAACCCGGGAAGCGGAGCUUGCAGUGAGCCGAGAUUGCGCCACUGCAGUCCGCAGUCCGGCCUGGGCGACAGAGCGAGACUCCGUCUCAAAAAAAAAAAAAAAAAAAAAAAAAGCUGUAGGCAAAAGGUAGCUCUACUCUCCUUUGCAAAUGCCUUGCAGGCUCACUUAAGAUACCAUCAUCAGAUAGAAGGAGGAAAGAGUAUUAAGAAUGCUGUGAGAGGUUAUUGAUGUGGAUCACUUCAGCCUGGCCCAUACAUUUACUCACAUUUCAUUGGCCAGAAUGCAGAUGUAUGCUCCUAUGUCACAUCUAAUUGCGUGGGAGCUGGGAAACGUAGUCUAGCUAUAUAUGCAGGAAGCAGAGAAACACAUUUUAGAGAACAGCUGGCCUUCUCUGCCUUAUCCUAAUUAUCCUCCCCCAAAGUAAACCACUAUUCAUUUGUAUGUAAUUUUAAAUAGAUAUUUAUCAAUUAAUAGAAAAUCAGGAUACAUACCUGACAAUUCAUGAUGUUGUCCUUUGGGGAAAGGAGUCAGGUUGAGAGAGGUAUUAAGUAGGACCUUCACUUUUUUUCUUUAUAUUUUUAUCUAAUUUCUAUUCUAUUUUCUGACUCGUAUUUAUGUAUUGCUUUUGCAAUUAAAAAUUAAAUCAUUAAAGACCAGAUAAAUGAAGGGAAAGAAUUCUGUAAAGUGUAUGCAAUAGUUUGAUUACUUUGAUUAAGCACAAAGUUCUCCCAGCAUUACUACUCACUUUCAUGUUUUGUUUUGUAAAUCUUGUUCUUGUGAUUUCUUAAAUGGGUUUUGUGUAUCCCAAUAGAUUAUCUCUCACUCUCUUACUUACAUAGGCUCUGUGAGUGCUUAUAGGUGUGUGAAUGUCAUUUGCUCAUACCCAGUUAUGUGAAACUGACUUAAGCAAAAUAAUACUUCUUUAGAUUGUCCUAUAACCCAUAUUGCUAAACACAUGGCAGAGACUCAGGAAAUAUUUGUUGCCUGCAUGAAUGCAUGCAUGCAUGUACGAAUGAUUACUUACCUAAACCUCAUGGUGGCAAAGUUCAGGUUUGUGAAGCUAUUGCAAAAUACAUGUAGAAUGCAUUAUUAGAUUGUACUUAUACAGACAGUUCCUAAGACACGCUGAGGUUUUAUUUCCAAAUGUGUUGUAUAACAUGAAUUAUUCAUAAGUCAGAGUCAUGUAGACUUAAGAUAAUUAUGCAUAUUGAAUAUCCAUCUGUACUACUGUAGUAGUUCUUAACAUCACCAGGGGUGCUUUUAAGAAACGCAGAUUCCCAGAUCCCACUCCAGACAUGCUCAAUUAGAGUCAGAGGCCUGAGUCCAGUAAUUUCUAGGAAGCACCACAGAUGAUUCUCAUAUAGCCAGCCCCACACUGGUCUUCCCACUGGCAUUCUGGAAACUAUUGUUCUAUGAAAUCUGGAAUGGUAUCUGCCAAGUCUUUCCCUAGUAAACACCACCAUAGUCUGUGUGGGGUUUUUUAUCCCCUUUUUAUUUAAGAAACAUUUCAAACACACAGAAAAUAUGCAUCAACCACUAAGCUCAUAUUGUUAAGAUAUUACUUAUAUUUGGUUAAUUAAAAAAGAUAAAUAUUACAGAGACAGCUAGCUGUCCCUCCACCCUCAUCCCUUCCUUCUCUGUCUUUCUCUAGCAGUAACCACUGUCCUGGUAUGUAAUAUUUGUCAAUGUGCGUUAACCAAAAACUACCAGGAAUAUACCUGUAGUUGAACAAGUUGGGUUUAUUACUCAUUGCAGCAAAGGAAAAUGCAUACCAUAGGGAAUGGUGAGUUAUCUCAGGGAGAAAGUGUUAGAAAGACCCUACUACAGGAUUUGUGCUUUGGUUGGGUAAUUUUGGGGAGGGUCUACGGAGGCAGGGAGUUGCUCUGGAUUGAGUGCCAUCAGAAUGUGGGGACAGUUUUAUGAUUGGGUAUCUCAAUAAAUCUUACCUAUAGGAAGGACCUAGAGUGACUACGAAGCUGUAAUUAGUGAAGAAGUAGUGGUCAUUCACUUAGAGGAGAUGAUGUUUGGUACUUUGUAGAUUGCAUGAUGACCUUGUGUGAAGUAGAUAUUCUGUGUGACUAUUUACAUCCAACAGUGGAACAAGGCUUAACUUCAGUGUCAGAUCAAAUCAGUUUAUAAUAACACUGAGAUUUAGACGUGAGCAUCAGAUCAGUUCCUGGAUGCCAGGAGCUGCUCUUCUCACUUGGCAAGUGUUUCUAAUUUUACUACAUAUAAGUGAAUUCACAAAAAGCAUAGACUGCUUUUUAAAAUACCAUUGUGUCAUAAUUUGAAAGGCAGCCUCCUCCACUCAGGUAUUUAGGAACCAAAACUGAUAGAGACUCCACCACCUUCAAUGCACAACUUCCAGCAUUUCCUUGAGGGCUGUCUCUGUUCCAGCCAGGAGAACAAUGUAUGGAGGCACAUGCAUGGGAAUUUUCUAAUAAGUUAGUACUGGAUGUGGCAUUCAACACUUCUCACAUUCCAUUGGUCAAGACUCAAUCAUAUAGCCAACCUUAGCUGCAAGGGAGGCUAGGAAAUGUAGCCAAGUUGUGUGGCCAGAAGAGGAGAAUGUAAAUUUUCAUGACCAUUUAGCAGUCUGCUACAACUGUAUUCUGUUGAGGCGAGAUUUUCCUGAAGGGACCUUUCAGGAUAUGCCAUAGAAAUCAACCUAAGAAUGAGCAGGAAGGACCCUUAAAGAUCCUAAGUUGGACAUAAGUAAAUUUUAUUUUGUUCUAUGGAGAAUAGAGGAAGAAAUCUUUCAUGCUUGGAUCAGAGUGACAAAGUGGAAGAGGACCACCCCUCUCCAACAGGCAGUAGAGUCACGGUAGUGAUAAUACCAAGAACCCCCAAGGGCAAGGUGAAAACAGUGCUAGAGUCCAGGGUUCUUAGUCCAGUUGGACUUCCCACGAGGAUGUUUUCCUUCGUUUGCCCCUCAAACAGGUUCUACAUCUUAUUUUUGUUAAAUAUAACCAGAGUUACCUACAGGGAUCCCACUUCAGUUCAGCCAAUAUAUGGAAAUUUUAUAUACCAGGGACUAAUGCUAAUAGUAGAAAAAUAUGAGUUAGUGUCGUAACAUGGGACUUCCUUUGUAUAGUUGAUCACUUGGCAGUAAUCCGCAUACUCUGCAGGCCCCUACCUGUAUUCCUCUGGCAGUCCUGUGACCCUGUCACUCUGCUUUAUAUCCUGCGGCAUGAGUGGGGCAGUGAUAAUUGGCACAAGGACCACAGAUAGAGGCUGGCUCUGCAGGCAGCUUUGUGCUUGGCGUUGGCAGGUAAGAAGCGGCAGUCAGUAAACUGAAGGGCUGCCUGUCAACUUGGUCUGAAGUUUCUUCCUUGCUUGUCACAGUGUUUCUUUUUCACUGCUUUCUCCUAUGGCCUGCACUUGGCUUAGGAUAUUCAGAGAUCUCAUCCAAACUUCUGGCAUCACUCUUCUUUUUAUACUUUUGACUGAUGACUUCAUAAAGCCCCAGACAAUGGGGCAGCUUCCACACUCUGUGACUUCAUUAGUCUCCUUGUCUAUUCUGGGCAAGAUAAGUAAUCUAAGACAAAUGGAAAGGCUGCUCGUCUCAACUGCUGAAUGUUUCUCAGGGUUCUCAAAACCGCUGAGUUCUUGAGCAAACUGAACACAGAAUCGCCAGACAGAAGUGCCUGUCAAAGUGCUGUUUGUGGCCCACAAUCCUCAACAUGGAAACUUCCUAUCCUGCCUAGGGAUCACAGCUGGGCCAGAAGCUGGGCUUACAGAGAUUCUCUAAAGGCAGAAGAAAACAGAAAAUUGCAAAAGAUGAAGGAUGAACAACAUCAAAAGAGUGAAUUACUGGAACUGAAACGGCAGCAGCAAGAGCAAGAAAGAGCCAAAAUCCACCAGACUGAACACAGGAGGGUAAAUAAUGCUUUUCUGGACCGACUCCAAGGCAAAAGUCAACCAGGUGGCCUCGAGCAAUCUGGAGGCUGUUGGAAUAUGAAUAGCGGUAACAGCUGGGGUUCUCUAUUAGUUUUUUCGAGGCACCUAAGGGUAUAUGAGAAAAUAUUGACUCCUAUCUGGCCUUCAUCAACUGACCUCGAAAAGCCUCAUGAGAUGCUUUUUCUUAAUGUGAUUUUGUUCAGCCUCACUGUUUUUACCUUAAUUUCAACUGCCCACACACUUGACCGUGCAGUCAGGAGUGACUGGCUUCUCCUUGUCCUCAUUUAUGCAUGUUUGGAGGAGCUGAUUCCUGAACUCAUAUUUAAUCUCUACUGCCAGGGAAAUGCUACAUUAUUUUUCUAAUUGGAAGUAUAAUUAGAGUGAUGUUGGUAGGGUAGAAAAAGAGGGAGUCACUUGAUGCUUUCAGGUUAAUCAGAGCUAUGGGUGCUACAGGCUUGUCUUUCUAAGUGACAUAUUCUUAUCUAAUUCUCAGAUCAGGUUUUGAAAGCUUUGGGGGUCUUUUUAGAUUUUAAUCCCUACUUUCUUUAUGGUACAAAUAUGUACAAAAGAAAAAGGUCUUAUAUUCUUUUACACAAAUUUAUAAAUAAAUUUUGAACUCCUUCUGUAUAAAUGGGUCAUUUUUAUUUUUAAUGAAAAGUUAUUGGGGUUUUCUCUCUUGAAGGGUCUCAUUUUAAUUCCCUUUUCCAGGCCGUAUAGAUCAAAUAUAGUACUGUCAUUACUGUUGGCUCUUGUUUUGGUCUUGACUUACUAAUAGUGUUACCCUGAUUUUCAGAGGGGGACAGUUUAUCUCCAGAAAGGCCAAUGUUUGUAUACACAUCAGCUAGACACAAAUAUAGACAUCAUAUGUAGUUUGUACAUGUUUCAGAAACUUGUUUUUUCUUUGCUCUGUGUAACCUAUUUCCUAUUGCUAGUUCAGUUGGCUUUCUUAUUCACUUCUGUGACCCUGAACCAGUUCUCAGACCCUAGAGUGUAAGAGCAUUGAUUUUCUACGCUGUGUAAUCUAGCUCAAUCCCUCUGUCCCCUCCGCCUCACCGUCCCCCAGCCACCACAUUGUAUAGCAAAAGCAUUACAUUCAAUCCUAGAAUAAAGGUAAAUACAACAAAUCAUCUUUGCAGCUGGACAACUAAUAAUACUUUGCAGCAUUAAGAGAUCUUCUGUGUUACCAGUCACUCUGUUGAAAUGAACUUUCCGAAUCUCUUUAUUCAGGAAAACAUGGGGUUUUGAAAUUCUUGGGCCAAGAGACAUAACUGAGGGGUUCGCAGAGCUAGGCAAGGGUGCACUAGGAAAGGGCCACAUUGGUGGGUGGGGGGUAACAGAGAACAGAUGGUGUCAGGAAGUUUCUCUGGAGUAAAUAAUGUGGAUAUUCUUGGUUUCCCUCUCCUCCGCCAGCUGAAGCUGUGUUAGUGCUGUUGACACUAAUAUAAAAUGUUUGGUCCAUUUGAAAUCCUUGUCAUUGCCUUAUAUGGGGGAAACUCAAUCCCCCAGCCUGUGUUGGAAAUAUCACCAAACUGAUUGUAAAUGUGCGGCUGUAGCAGACAUUUUAGUGUGGUGGUGUGCAGCCAUUUCGGCCCUACACCUGCCAGCCUGGCUACCUUACAGUUGUGUUCCGAUUUUUGCGUCUAUGCUUGGUGUGCCUCACUUGCUGCAUUUUCCAGCAUGCAACCAGGAGUUGACGUAGGAAAAAGGGAUGCUUUCUUACUUUGGAAGCUCUCAGGGAAGUUGGUGUCAAUUUCUCCUCCACUGCCUGGCCUACCCUGCACUCCCAAAGAUUUUGUGCAGAUGGGUAGUUCCAUUUUUUAAAAAUUGUGCAGAUAUGGAAAAUUGUGACUUACUUCAUGACCAGAACUAUCUAGAAUAUGUGUGGGGGUAUAAACAUCUUGCUUAACCAAAUAUCUAUGUAGGCAGAGGUAACCAGGAGAGAAGCAAGACUUGCUGCCUAAAGGAGCCCACCAUUUUACUUUUCACAUUUAAUCUGCCACGUUGAAUCAAUUGGAAUAAAACCUGACUCGCAGGUGACUGGACAGGAAAUCCCAAAGUUCCACCAUUUCUAUGCUUAAUUUUAAUGUCCCCCCGCUUUUUUUUUUGUAGAAAAUAAAAACAAGAAAAUCGUUCCAAUGUAAGAUGUUUGUUAUAGAAACUUUAGGCAAUACAGGUGUGUAAUAAAAUGUUUAAUAAACUUCUAAACACUUUUGUAUUUGGAUUUA